GCUAUUAUUCGUGAAUUGGGUGGUAUUCCAAUUGUUGCAAACAAAAUCAACCAUUCCAACCAGAGUAUUAAAGAGAAAGCUUUAAAUGCACUAAAUAACCUGAGUGUGAAUGUUGAAAAUCAAAUCAAGAUAAAGAUAUACAUCAGUCAAGUAUGUGAGGAUGUCUUCUCUGGUCCUCUGAACUCUGCUGUGCAGCUGGCUGGACUGACAUUGUUGACAAACAUGACUGUUACCAAUGACCACCAGCACAUGCUUCACAGUUACAUUACAGACCUGUUCCAGGUGUUACUUACUGGAAAUGGAAACACGAAGGUGCAAGUUUUGAAACUGCUUUUGAAUUUGUCUGAAAAUCCAGCCAUGACAGAAGGACUUCUCCGUGCCCAAGUGGAUUCAUCAUUCCUUUCCCUUUAUGACAGCCACGUAGCAAAGGAGAUUCUUCUUCGAGUACUUACGCUAUUUCAGAAUAUAAAGAACUGCCUCAAAAUAGAAGGCCAUUUAGCUGUGCAGCCUACUUUCACUGAAGGUUCAUUGUUUUUCCUGUUACAUGGAGAAGAAUGUGCCCAGAAAAUAAGAGCUUUAGUUGAUCACCAUGAUGCAGAGGUGAAGGAAAAGGUUGUAACAAUAAUACCCAAAAUCUGAUUGGUCAUAUUUUUCCAAAGAGUAAUGCAGUCUGGAUAUAAACGUAUUUUCUGUCUUCCUUAUAAGGGGAUUCUCCCAGCUGCUAAAUUUAAACAGUAAAUAUCACAUUUUGUCAUUAACACAGCUAUAACUUGCCGUGGUUCUCAGAUUUAUUUUGGACUAUUUUGAUGCCAAGUGAAUAUAAGAGCUUGUACUGAAACCAUUUAUUUCUUUCUAUUUUGCUAUUUGCAAAUGCUUGUUAUCUUCCCUACAUGAAGUGGCAGUAACCUUUUUCACAUUUAAGCUACCCUUCUACCUUUUGAAGUGAUUUGCAGUUACUCAUCUGAGACAGCAUCAGUAUUUGACUAAAUCAUUGUUUCACAACUGAAUAGUCUUGUUCUUUUAGUAGCAACGAAAUCCUAAGCUCUUGAGGCCAUUCACCUGCCAACCUGACCAUACUGCUUUCAAAAGUCUUUUCUCAUCAGUAGAAUCUAUUUUGGUCACUUCUAGUCAAUGAAAAAUGUAAACUUUUAGGAGAGAAUGUUUCUUAGGACUCACCCACUCCAUUCAAUGUUAUAUAUAAAAUAGUGUGAUCAAUCACAAUGUCCAUCUUUAGACAGUUGGUUAAAUAAAUUAUCUGGUCUUUGAAAAGACCGUGCUGGGCGCGGUGGCUCUUGCCUGUAAUCCCAGCACUUUGGGAGGCUGAGGCGGGCAGAUCACCUGAGAUCGGGAGUUUGAGACCAAGCCUGACCAAUAUGGAGAAACCCUGUCUCUACUAAGAACACAAAAUUAGCUGGGCAUGGUGGUGCAUGCCUGUAAUCCCAGCUACUUGGGAGGCCGAGGCAGGAGAAUUGCUUGAACCCGGGAGGCAGAGGUUGCAGUGAGCUGAGAUAGCGCCAUUGCACUCCAGCCUGGGCAACAAGAGCAAAACUCUGUCUCAAAAAAAAAAAAAAAUGAUGGAGCUCCGAAUGUGCUUAAGUGGAAAGAUAUCUAUGAAAUAUGGUGGUUUUUUAAAACACAAAAAUUAUAGAAUAUGGGAUCCCGUGUGUGUGUGUGUGUGUUUGAAUGAAAAAUGCUUAUGUAUUGACAGAACACUUCUAGAAUGAUACCCAAACUCCUGGAGUGGGAGUGGGGAAUGCCUUCUACGUACACACUGUUCUACUGUUUGAAUUUUUUAAUAUGAGCCCAAAUUGUAUAAUCUUUUUUUAAUAAAGGGGAGAAAAAUCA